AUUGAGGGAAGAAGGGAGAAAACAGAAAACUGAUGGAGUUCCCACUGCGUGUCGGCCACUGGAGAUUUCAAAGGUUUCUUGUUUAACUCAAGCUACCAAAAUCGCCUACCAUUUGGUGCAAGCAAAAAGCAAUCAGCAAUUGGACAGGAAAAGAAUGGCAUUGAAGCAGAUUUCCAGCAACAAGUGCUUUGGGGGAUUGCAGAAAGUUUUUGAACAUGACAGUGUUGAACUAAACUGCAAAAUGAAAUUUGCUGUCUACUUACCACCAAAGGCAGAAACAGGAAAGUGCCCUGCACUGUAUUGGCUCUCAGGUUUAACUUGCACAGAGCAAAAUUUUAUAUCAAAAUCUGGUUAUCAUCAGUCUGCUUCAGAACAUGGUCUUGUUGUCAUUGCUCCAGAUACCAGCCCUCGUGGCUGCAAUAUUAAAGGUGAAGAUGAGAGCUGGGACUUUGGCACUGGUGCUGGAUUUUAUGUUGAUGCCACUGAAGAUCCUUGGAAAACCAACUACAGAAUGUACUCUUAUGUCACAGAGGAGCUUCCCCAACUCAUAAAUGCCAAUUUUCCAGUGGAUCCCCAAAGGAUGUCUAUUUUUGGCCACUCCAUGGGAGGUCAUGGAGCUCUGAUCUGUGCUUUGAAAAAUCCUGGAAAAUACAAAUCUGUGUCAGCAUUUGCUCCAAUUUGCAACCCUGUACUCUGUCCCUGGGGCAAAAAAGCCUUUAGUGGAUAUUUGGGAACAGAUCAAAGUAAAUGGAAGGCUUAUGAUGCUACCCACCUUGUGAAAUCCUAUCCAGGAUCUCAGCUGGACAUACUAAUUGAUCAAGGGAAAGAUGACCAGUUUCUUUUAGAUGGACAGUUACUCCCUGAUAACUUCAUAGCUGCCUGUACAGAAAAGAAAAUCCCCGUUGUUUUUCGAUUGCAAGAGGGUUAUGAUCAUAGCUACUACUUCAUUGCAACCUUUAUUACUGACCACAUCAGACAUCAUGCUAAAUACCUGAAUGCAUGAAAAAACUCCAAAUAAGAGAAUCUCUUCAGGAUUAUAAAAGUUGUAAAAUGCAACUGUAUUGCUGAGCAAAAAAAAAAAAAAUUCAAAACAUUGGAUUUUAUAGUGCUAAAAGGGCUUUAUUCUAUAGUUGAAUCACCUCUGAAUAAAGAUAUAAAACCUA